AGACUCGCUGAGUCGCUCCUGCAGAAAGGGGGGGAGAGAGAUCGAAAAGCAGGGGAGGGGGACGGCACGGCCGUUUACCUGUCUGCCUCCUCAUUCGCUCUCCCCCCUCGUUCUGCUCACUCCUGGUGUCAGCCUAUCCGCCUUCCCAAACCCUCCCAUUCCCCCGGUGUAGCCCCCCCCUUCACUUUCCUUCUCGUCCUCUGUGUUUCUCCUCUCUUCUUUCUUCCCUUCCCCCUCUAGCAUUGCUACCUUCUCUCCUACACGCACGCAGGCAUAUAAACGUAGGUUUUUGAUGCUCCUCUGCCUGUUGACCCCGCUAUUUUCAUGUUUCCAACAGGUUUUUCUUCCCCCAGUCCCUCAGCUGCUGCUGCUGCUCAGGAGGUCAGAUCUGCCACUGAUGGUAAUACCAGCACCACUCCGCCCACCUCUGCCAAGAAGAGAAAGUUAAACAGCAGCAGCAGUAGCAGCAGUAACAGUAGUAACGAGAGAGAAGACUUUGAUUCCACCUCUUCCUCCUCUUCCACUCCUCCUUUACAACCCAGGGAUUCGGCAUCCCCUUCAACCUCGUCCUUCUGCCUGGGGGUUUCAGUGGCUGCUUCCAGCCACGUACCGAUACAGAAGAAGCUGCGUUUUGAAGACACCCUGGAGUUUGUAGGGUUUGAUGCGAAGAUGGCUGAGGAAUCCUCCUCCUCCUCCUCCUCAUCUUCACCAACUGCUGCAACAUCUCAGCAGCAGCAACUUAAAAAUAAGAGUAUAUUAAUCUCUUCUGUGGCUUCGGUGCAUCAUGCAAACGGCCUAGCCAAAUCUUCUACCACCGUCUCUAGCUUUGCUAACAGCAAACCUGGCUCUGCUAAGAAGUUAGUGAUCAAGAACUUUAAAGAUAAGCCUAAAUUACCAGAAAACUACACAGAUGAAACCUGGCAAAAACUGAAAGAAGCAGUGGAAGCUAUUCAGAAUAGUACUUCAAUUAAGUACAAUUUAGAAGAACUCUACCAGGCUGUAGAAAAUCUCUGUUCUUACAAGAUUUCUGCAAACUUGUACAAACAGCUGAGACAGAUCUGCGAAGAUCACAUCAAAGCACAGAUUCAUCAAUUCAGAGAGGAUUCAUUGGAUAGCGUUCUUUUUUUAAAGAAGAUUGAUAGAUGCUGGCAAAACCAUUGCAGACAAAUGAUCAUGAUCAGGAGCAUUUUUUUGUUUCUGGAUAGAACUUACGUUCUUCAGAAUUCAAUGCUACCCUCCAUUUGGGACAUGGGACUGGAGUUAUUUAGGGCUCAUAUUAUAAGUGAUCAGAAAGUGCAGAAUAAGACAAUUGAUGGCAUUCUUCUCUUGAUUGAGAGGGAAAGGAAUGGUGAAGCAAUUGAUAGAAGUUUACUUCGAAGCCUUUUAAGCAUGCUGUCUGAUUUGCAAAUUUAUCAAGAUUCUUUUGAACAACGAUUUUUGGAAGAAACUAACCGGCUCUAUGCAGCUGAAGGCCAAAAAUUAAUGCAAGAAAGAGAGGUUCCUGAAUAUCUACAUCAUGUUAACAAACGUCUAGAAGAAGAAGCAGACAGACUUAUUACUUACUUAGAUCAGACCACCCAGAAGUCAUUAAUUGCUACUGUAGAAAAACAACUUCUAGGUGAACACUUAACAGCAAUUCUUCAGAAAGGUUUAAAUAACCUCCUUGAUGAAAACCGAAUUCAAGAUUUGUCUCUUCUGUAUCAGCUCUUCAGUAGAGUUCGAGGUGGAGUUCAGGUUCUUUUGCAGCAGUGGAUCGAAUAUAUCAAGGCAUUUGGCAGCACUAUUGUAAUUAAUCCUGAAAAAGAUAAAACCAUGGUUCAAGAAUUGCUGGAUUUUAAAGAUAAGGUUGACCAUAUAAUUGAUAUCUGCUUUCUGAAGAAUGAGAAAUUUAUCAAUGCCAUGAAAGAAGCAUUUGAAACGUUCAUUAACAAAAGACCAAAUAAACCAGCUGAACUUAUAGCUAAGUAUGUAGAUUCAAAACUUCGUGCAGGCAACAAAGAAGCUACAGAUGAAGAACUUGAGAAAAUGUUGGAUAAAAUUAUGAUCAUAUUUAGAUUUAUCUAUGGCAAGGAUGUUUUUGAGGCCUUCUAUAAGAAAGAUUUAGCCAAGCGCCUGUUAGUCGGAAAGAGUGCAUCUGUAGAUGCUGAAAAAUCAAUGCUGUCCAAACUUAAACAUGAAUGCGGAGCUGCUUUCACCAGCAAACUUGAAGGAAUGUUUAAAGACAUGGAACUUUCUAAAGACAUCAUGAUUCAGUUCAAACAGUAUAUGCAGAAUCAGAAUGUUCCGGGAAAUAUUGAGUUAACUGUGAAUAUCCUGACAAUGGGCUAUUGGCCGACAUAUGUGCCUAUGGAAGUUCAUUUACCACCAGAGAUGGUAAAACUUCAGGAGAUUUUCAAGACAUUUUACCUAGGCAAACAUAGUGGCAGGAAACUUCAGUGGCAGUCAACCCUAGGACACUGUGUGUUAAAAGCAGAAUUUAAAGAGGGUAAAAAGGAACUCCAGGUCUCUCUUUUUCAAACACUGGUGCUGCUAAUGUUUAAUGAGGGAGAGGAGUUCAGUUUAGAAGAGAUCAAGCAGGCAACUGGAAUAGAGGAUGGAGAGUUAAGGAGAACACUGCAGUCAUUAGCCUGUGGCAAAGCUAGAGUUCUGGCGAAAAAUCCAAAGGGCAAAGACAUUGAAGAUGGUGACAAGUUCAUUUGUAAUGAUGAUUUCAAACAUAAACUUUUCAGGAUAAAGAUCAAUCAAAUCCAGAUGAAAGAAACGGUUGAAGAACAAGCAAGCACUACAGAAAGAGUAUUUCAAGACAGACAGUAUCAAAUUGAUGCUGCAAUUGUUCGAAUUAUGAAGAUGAGAAAGACACUUAGCCACAAUCUCCUUGUUUCAGAAGUGUACAACCAGUUGAAAUUUCCAGUAAAGCCUGCUGAUCUUAAGAAGAGAAUAGAAUCUUUAAUUGACCGGGACUACAUGGAAAGAGAUAAAGAAAAUCCAAACCAGUACAACUAUAUUGCAUAGAAUGUUGGCCUUGCAGCAUUUGGUGUCAUAUGCAGUAGCCAGUGGAUAAACUAACCUGUUGAUUCAAUAUUAUUUGACUCCUUUUUUACUACCGAUGACCAAAUGAAGCAGUGUAAUUAAUGGAAAUAGUUGAGUGGACUUUUUCUCAGUGGUUAACAUGCCCAUUUUAAAGAGUAAUACUUACCUUUAAGAAGAAUGUUGUUGAACUCUUUGCAUGUUAUUUAGUAUGAUGUGCAGAAAACACUUAAGAACGUACCUGGUCUUCAUGAAUUCCUCUUUGGAACUGGGAAAGAGAUCCCUGUGGCUAUUAAAAAGGGGGGAGGGUUCUUACACACCAUUAAUUAUGAAGCAAAAGGUUUAUUUGCUUAAAAUGUCAUUUAAAGAUACUUAAACUGCAUGCAAACUUUAUUUACUGUACAGAGUUCUGGAUGUAUUUAUCAAAUAGAAAAACCACCCUUGACUUGGUUGUUCACCCGUUUUGUGAUUUCCCUUGAAAAGAGAAAUGAAUUGUCAUAGCUAUUGAUAUUUUACUAGGUGAUGUUCUGUUACACUGAAAGGGAUGUUUUUUAAAAAAAAUUAUUUGGAAACAAGUUUUCAAGUAGGGGGACAGUUGCUUACAUAAUAUCUUGUAUAUUCACAUCCUAAAAAUUUUCAUUUAUGAGUAUGGGAUGUGUGUAUAUGGCUUAGCCCCAAGUUAACUGUGCUGAUUAACAAGUACUUAUAAAAAUAGCUAAAGUAGAAAAUUAAUGAUCAGUUGUACUAGAGGAACAUCAUAGAAGAGAAAAAUCCAACUCUUUAUAUUAAAAAUGAAUACAAUAAGAAAAUUGCAAAAGAGACCAAAAUGAACGUGUUUUGUAAAUUGUUACAGGAGCAAAAACUUUGCAACUAGUUUUCAACAUACUUUAGACUUUAAAUGUUGUUUGGACAGUUUUGUCUUCAACUUGGACCAAUUGUAGAUUGUUACAGGCUUCCUAGGAUUUAGCAUUCCUAUUUUCUCUACCAAAGUUUUUUUUAGAAGCAUCCCAACUCUUCUCUUUGUUGAUAAAUAAGCCUUUCCUGUCAUCUUCAUUUUAACUUGCUAAAACCCUAGAUACAAAGGUCCUCCCUCAUUUUUCCCACAGAGCCCCUGUUUGGGAAUUUGAGAUUCUGUGUCAUGCUGGUUUUCCUUUCAGAAUUGCUUGAAAUCGAGUUCUCUUAGCCACUGGACACCUAGUUUUCAGGAGAAUGUCCCAAGAUUGUUUAUAUAUACAAAAUGGCAAAAGUACUGUUUUUCGAAUUGAUAAUUCAAGCAAAGGCUUCUCUUUACUGUCACUGAUUUUUUUUUGUUUUUAUUUUGUUUCCUUGUUUCUAUUUCCUUGAAGCUUUGAAGGGAGGAGAAGCAGAAAAUUUUGUUUAUGUUUGUUAAAAAUCAGAACUACUUAAUGCUUUUUGCCACAGCAUAUUUCCUUGCCUGUUGGAGCCGUUAGGAAGAUUACCUAUGUCCUAAUCUUCAACCUGAGAAGAUUUUUGACUCUUGUGUCUACUGUUGAUUGUUUGCUUGAGUUCUCAAAGACCUGUGGCCAGGUAUUUUAAAAAGUCGUCUAUUUCUUUCUAGUUGCAUCAACUUGCACACUGGUGUCUAACUAUAUGUGGUAUUCGGAACUUGUAAUUCUUAUUGAGCAGCCAUUGCCUAUAUUUUCUCAGCUCCUCACUGAUUUCUUUAUAUGAGCUCAGCUGACAAGCAAAUGCAGCUAUUUUGUUUACCCUCUCUUCAUACCGGACCAUCAACAACAGUGUUCUAACUCAUCCCUGAUGGUCUGUGAGAUGUAGACUAUUACACAAGAUUCAAGUUACUCGUAAGCAACUUUUAGAUAGAGUUGGUCCUGUUAGGAGGAGACUCUUGAUGUCACCUUCAGUAUCUUGAAAGCGGGUCCCCUCCCCGAGGCUCUUAAUUCUUUGAAAACUUGAUGCUGUUUCAGCUGAAAAAUUAGCAAGACUGUUAAAAAAAAAAAGUUGAGGGGAGCUGUUUAAGAAACUGAAAAGUAAUUGCAAACUACAUUGGAUAAUUGUGACUUUCAGUUGUUGUUCUGUAUCAGUUGAAUUUUUGUGCUCUUUUCCCUGUGUACGUGGUGGUUCUAUUUUUCUCCAAUAAAACUUUUAUUUAAAAAAAGUUUCUAGAGAAGAUCUUUAAAAUUCAAGUAUUGUAAGAAAGUUAUAAAAUCACAGGACUUAAAAUCUUCCUAACAACUUCUAAUGAACUCACAUUUGUUGAUUUUGUUAUUUUUAAACUUUUUAAAAAUUUUGUAAUGGUUUUGUGGUAAUGCUAUAAGAGUAUGGGGGAGGGCAUGGUUAACAGGGUGAGGAAAAUUCCCAGGAAUCCUCAAGGUGGAUAAUUAUUCUUAAACAUGCGGAUACAAGUAUAAACAUUGCUUCAUUCAAAUCCUCAGUGUCAAAUUGUUUCAUAAAGUCAAUAUGAAAUGAGUCUAGAUUUGAGUUCAGGGGAGAAGAAAAGAUUACUCUUAGUUAUGGCAUUUGCUCUGCCUUUUCUGUUAAUAGUUUUUUGAGUUCUGGGCCAGAUACUCUCAGAGUAAGAUGUUCCUCAAAGUUUUUGAACCCAGUUCCUGAGUCUGCUUGAAUGGUCUUAAUAUGAUGUCUAGCCAUACUCUUGAAAUUUUUGCUGUGUAUGUGAGUGUACAGUUCAGAAAACCAGUUUAUCUGGGCAUCUGGAUCUAAAGAUUUGAGAAGUUUGUUUUUUAAUCUGGAUAUUCAUAAAUCUUUUAAAAUGAGCUGGUCUUUGUUUUCAUGACCACUCUGUUUAAUGCUGUGAAUGGCAGGAGUGUUGUGAGCGUGUUCUAUUCUCUUAUUUACAUAAAAUUGCCAAAACAAAUUGUUCAUUAAAAAGAAAAGAGCAGUACUGAUGAAAA